ACAGCUGGCAUUCAGCCUCCAGAGCACCAGCACUGGCACUGGCACUGGCACACGCUAUGGCAAAUGAAGUGCAAGACCUGCUCUCCCCUCGGAAAGGGGGACAUCCUCCUGCAGUAAAAGCUGGAGGAAUGAGAAUUUCCAAAAAACAAGAAAUUGGCACCUUGGAAAGACAUACCAAAAAAACAGGAUUCGAGAAAACAAGUGCCAUUGCAAAUGUUGCCAAAAUACAGACACUGGAUGCCCUGAAUGACGCACUGGAGAAGCUCAACUAUAAAUUUCCAGCAACAGUGCACAUGGCGCAUCAAAAACCCACACCUGCUCUGGAAAAGGUUGUUCCACUGAAAAGGAUCUACAUUAUUCAGCAGCCUCGAAAAUGUUAAGCCUGGAUUUAAAACACAGCCGUCUGGCCAGCUGCCUCGAAUAUCUGACAGCUUAGCAAAAAGGGCCAAAGCUUUCCAUAGGCGUGCUGCACUUGCUUGGUAAAUUAAGCAGCUUUUGUAUCUUCCCCUUUGACUUUAGGUAAUAAAGCAUCCAAACUUGUAAAUCUGA